AAUUUUAACCAUUGUAAAAGACCAUGAAGAUUCUUGGAAACCUGAAUAAAGCUAUAUUCAGUUGGAAGCUCUUGAAGGGUUUUAUACAUGGAAAUGACAUUAUUUGGGUUUUUAAAUGAUCACUCCGGUUGUAAUAUAGAAAAUGAUAUGGAAGGAGGCUGGGUAAAUGUGUGAAGGCCUUUGGGAGAAUAUCAUGUUAGUAUAGGGGAGAGGGAAGAUACCUUGAUUUGAGAGGUAGCAGUGGAGAUGAAGUGACUAGAUAUGGAAAUGUUUUAGAAGAUGGAACUGAUAAACUCAGUGAUUGAGCAGAUAUAGGACUUAAGAGACGGGGAGCUCUCAAGGUUGUUUCCACAUUUCUGGCACCAGCAACUACAUUUAUAAUGACACCCUUACUGAGAUGAGGAACAUUGACAGAGAAAAAGGUUUGAGAAGAUAAAGUAAUUGGGUCAAUUUUGAGAUAUAUGUAAGACAUCCAAAUGGAGGUCUCAAGUAGGCAGUGUGAGAUCUGGGUUCCUGAAUGGUGGAACAAAAUUAGAAAUUAUUGUGGUAUAAAGGAUAUUUGAUGAUAUGGGGUACAUAAGAUUUUCUCUCUCUCUCUUACUGUCUGUUGAGUUUAGUGAUUUGAGGAGAGUGAAUUGGAUAGACCUAAGAGGAAAUUUGGUGUUUAAUUUUGGGCAGUAGAGUGACUCACAAAGGAAGCUAAGAGAGAGUGGUUCAAAGAGGCUGGAGAGAGAGAGAGUUGUCCCCCAGAUGCCCAGGUGAGUGAACAAUCAUUUGUGCAUUUAUUGGAUUUGGUGGCAUAGUUGGCAUUUAGUCAGUUUUGUGGUUGUUGGUAGUGGUUGGAUGUAUGUGAAAAUUCAAAUUAGGGUGAGUGUGAGGAGUAAGGAGUGAGGCAGUAGAAAAAAAACAAGAUUUACAGGUCUAUCGGGAAUUUUUAGGAUAGUUGUUAGAGAUACAUGUAAGAGGUGUUUAUUAUUGUUGAGACUGAGAUAGGUUAGAGCUUGGUGAUGAGAAGGACAAGGGAGGGAGUGAAUAUAGGAGAAACUGUUGUUAAUGGAAUGAGAUCCUCACACACUAGUGAUGCCUUUCAGAUCCAGCAAACUUGAUGAAGGGAAAACUCAGUCAAGAUUAAUGUUCACAGUUAGAGUAGAAUAGAGGACUUUUAGUAUUACCAAGUUCUAAUGAACUAUAUCAUAAUAUGGUCUUUAAACUUAUUUCUCAAGUAUUUCUCGAAAACUUACCAAGCAGAAAAUGUCAGCAAUCUUUCUGAUGUGUGAAAAUGCUCUGGCGGUUUAGUCACUUGUCAGUCUCAUGUCCAAGUCCUACCCAUCUGUCCUGGCGCAAUUGAAACCCUCAAAUGAAAGACUCUCCCUCCCUCAUCUGAAUGGCCAUAGCCUGGUGUUUUUUUCCCUCUAGGGUGGCAUUUAUUCUUUCUAUGUACUUGUUAUAUAUAUGUAUGUGUGUGUGUGUGUGUGUGUGUGUGUGUGUGUAUAAUUUUUUUCCUCAUUAGAUGGAAGGCAAAGACCAUAAUUGAAAUAUGUUAAUGUUCUCUGUAGUACCUACUGGUUACAUUUAUUUAGUUAACAAACUAAAUGUAUAUAAAGGUAAAAAAUAGGGACAUGGUUAUUAGCAGAUAAUUAAAAGAAGCUAUAUGAAAAAUAAGAUUUUUGUGGUUUGGUGUCAGAAUUUGUAGCCUGAUAAUAAGUUUUUGUUUUUAUGAAAUUUAGUAAAACAUGUUUUGAAAGUUCCUAAUCAUAUGUGACUAAAAGAUCAAAUUAUUUAACAGAGUGAUAACAGCAACAACUCUGGUGGUUACUUUGUCAUUUACCAGUGACUUUCAGAUUAUUAUUCCAUUCAGACUGAGGAUAAUCCAAAGAUACAAGGAGAAAUCACAGGGAUUUUUGUCACCAUUUUACAAGUGAAGAAACCAGAGAUAAUGAGUCAACAGUUACAUUGCUGGUAACCAGGUGCUAAAUCCCAGGCUGGGAUCUUCUGAUCCUAAUGUGGGUUUCUUUCAGUUUACCCAAUGGCUUCUAGAUUUACUUUCAUAGAAAUCCAAUUGGCCUGAUAAUAAUUAAAUGCAACUGCAGGGGGUAAGUGGGUUUCCUUUAUUUGAAUGAAUUUAAAAAAUCACUUAUUUUGGGUGAUUAGGAUAAUCUCUUGGUAACGCCUGAGAUUACCUCCUCUUGCACAUGCUUUGGCCUGUUGGCCUAGAGCUUCAAAUGGGGCUCCUGCAGCAGAAUGGGAAAAACACCACCAUCAUGGAUUGCAAUGAUGCUGUGAUUUGAAGAAAAGAAAAUGGAAGUCACAUAUCUGUGGAAUACUAAUAGAGCAAUGCUGGCCAGUACUGUUUGCUAUAGUGAACAAACCUAGUAUUAGCAUUUUGGAAAAAAACCAAACACCAUUUUCCUGGGUUUCUGACUCUGCCUUCUGGCAACUACUUAUUUUUAAAGUCCAGGAUCAUUUUUUAUUUAGGAUGAAAAGCUACAUUCUUUAAGAAACUAGAAAUAUGGAAGGUCAUUAUUUUUUAGGAGGACUAUGUCAGGGCCUUUAAUUAUAUUAUUGUUGAAGUUUCAUAAAAACUGUAAUAAUGGGCUGGGUGCAGUGGCUCAUGCCUGUAAUCUCAGCAGUUUGGAAGGCCGAGGCAGAUGGAUUGCUUGAUUGAUUCUAGGAGUUCGAGACCACGCUGGGCAACAUGGUGAAACCCCAUCUCUUCAAAAAAUACGAAAAUCAGCCAGGCUUGGUGGCGCACACCUGUAGUCCCAGCUACUCUGUAGGCUGAGGUGGCAGAUUCACCUGAACGUGGGGAGGAUGAGGUUGCAGUAAGCUGUGAUAGUGCCACCGCACCCCAGGCUGGGCAACAGAAUGAAGCCCCAUAUCAAAAAAAUCCAACAAACUGUAAUGAAUAUAGUUUUGUCAGGAGAACUGAGGAAUGAAGAAUGUAUACUUCUGAGAAAGUGUGGAAAGACAUGAAGUCCUUUUUCCUCCUCCUUCACCACUUUAAUAUGUCAUCUGAAUGAAUUGCUAGUACUGGAUGAACCUGGCCUAUGUUAAAGCAGCAGACUGCAUUUCAGAACCAGUUAACAGGGAGCCUCCUUCCAGAGAAGCUCAGCUACUGACUUUGCAAAACACAUCUGAAUUUGAUAUCCUUGUUAUUGGAGGAGGAGCAACAGGAAGUGGCUGUGCGCUAGAUGCUGUCACCAGAGGACUAAAAACAGCCCUUGUAGAAAGAGAUGAUUUCUCAUCAGGGACCAGCAGCAGAAGCACUAAAUUGAUCCAUGGUGGUGUGAGAUAUCUGCAGAAGGCCAUCAUGAAGUUGGAUAUUGAGCAGUAUAGGAUGGUAAAAGAAGCCCUUCAUGAGCGUGCCAACCUGCUAGAAAUUGCUCCCCAUUUAUCAGCUCCAUUGCCUAUAAUGCUUCCAGUUUACAAGUGGUGGCAGUUACCUUACUACUGGGUAGGAAUCAAGCUGUAUGAUUUGGUUGCAGGAAGCAAUUGCCUAAAAAGCAGUUAUGUCCUCAGCAAAUCAAGAGCCCUUGAACAUUUCCCAAUGCUCCAGAAGGACAAACUGGUAGGAGCAAUUGUCUACUAUGACGGACAACAUAACGAUGCACGGAUGAACCUUGCCAUUGCUCUGACUGCUGCCAGGUAUGGGGCUGCCACAGCCAAUUACAUGGAGGUAGUGAGCUUGCUCAAGAAGACAGACCCCCAGACAGGGAAAGUGCGUGUGAGCGGCGCACGGUGCAAGGAUGUCCUCACAGGGCAGGAAUUUGACGUGAGAGCCAAAUGUGUUAUCAAUGCCACGGGACCUUUCACGGACUCUGUGCGCAAAAUGGAUGAUAAAGACGCAGCAGCUAUCUGCCAGCCAAGUGCUGGUGUCCAUAUUGUGAUGCCUGGUUAUUACAGCCCAGAGAGCAUGGGACUUCUUGACCCAGCGACCAGUGAUGGGCGAGUUAUUUUCUUCUUACCCUGGCAAAAGAUGACGAUCGCUGGCACUACUGAUACUCCAACUGAUGUUACACACCAUCCAAUUCCUUCAGAAGAAGAUAUCAACUUCAUUUUGAAUGAAGUGCGUAAUUACCUGAGUUGUGAUGUUGAAGUGAGAAGAGGGGAUGUCCUGGCAGCAUGGAGUGGAAUCCGUCCUCUUGUUACAGACCCCAAAUCUGCAGAUACUCAGUCUAUCUCCCGAAAUCAUGUUGUUGAUAUCAGUGAGAGUGGCCUUAUUACUAUAGCAGGUGGAAAGUGGACAACUUAUCGGUCUAUGGCAGAAGAUACCAUAAAUGCUGCUGUCAAAACUCAUAAUUUAAAAGCAGGACCAAGUAGAACAGUUGGGCUUUUCCUUCAAGGGGGUAAAGAUUGGAGCCCCACACUCUACAUUAGGCUUGUGCAGGAUUAUGGACUUGAAAGCGAGGUGGCACAGCAUCUUGCCGCCACCUAUGGUGAUAAGGCCUUUGAGGUGGCCAAAAUGGCAAGUGUGACUGGCAAAAGGUGGCCUAUUGUUGGAGUACGUCUUGUGUCAGAAUUUCCAUAUAUUGAAGCAGAGGUGAAAUAUGGGAUUAAGGAGUAUGCCUGCACUGCUGUGGAUAUGAUUUCACGUCGUACUCGCCUGGCCUUUCUAAAUGUCCAGGCAGCAGAGGAAGCCCUACCCAGGAUUGUUGAACUGAUGGGCAGGGAACUGAAUUGGGAUGAUUAUAAGAAGCAGGAACAACUUGAAACAGCCAGGAAGUUUCUAUAUUAUGAAAUGGGCUAUAAAUCUCGAUCAGAACAGUUAACAGAUCGCUCUGAAAUUAGCCUACUGCCUUCAGACAUUGACAGGUAUAAGAAGAGAUUUCAUAAGUUUGAUGCAGACCAGAAAGGCUUUAUUACCAUUGUUGAUGUUCAGCGUGUAUUAGAGAGUAUCAAUGUCCAAAUGGAUGAAAAUACACUCCAUGAAAUUCUAAAUGAAGUUGAUUUGAAUAAAAAUGGACAGGUUGAACUCAAUGAAUUUUUGCAGCUGAUGAGUGCUAUUCAAAAAGGAAGGGUAUCUGGAAGCCGGCUUGCUAUACUAAUGAAAACUGCAGAAGAGAACCUCGACAGAAGAGUUCCAAUUCCAGUGGACCGUAGUUGUGGAGGAUUGUGAGUCUGGGCAGUAAAUCCACAGCCAACAAACAUAGAAACGACAAAUCACCAUGUAACAACCAGAGAUGACUGAAACCACUCUGAAAUAAUGAAUGUGGAUAGCUGCCUUUUUUAACACUAGAAAACAUUCCAAAACUUUAAGGUGUUGGUGUAUUUGCCAGCUUUAUUUGCUGUACUUUAUUUGUAUUUGCCAUUCAGUCUAGCUUUUAAGUAUAUUUUUUUCUUUUUCUCAUUUUCAAUGCACAUUAGUUUUGCAUCUGUUUUGUGACCUGUUAGAUGUGACACAUUCUCUUUUUGUUUAUUCCCUUAUUCUAAAUGAGUUCUAAAAACAUAAUAUUUUGGCAAAAAUUGAAAAAAGCUGGAGACAUUUUGUGACAUGCAUACAGAUAGCAUGUGUUAUUAAAAAGAGUUGCCUAUUGAAAUGAUCAUGUUUCUGGAGAAAUUAAGCUUAUAGACAGCAUGUGUUAUUAAAAAGAGUUACCUAUUGAAAUGAUAGUGUUUCUGGAGAUUUCUCAGCCCCAUCUUCCUCCAGCUUGUCUACCUUCCUCAUGCAAACAAUAUUCCACAUUUUUAUAUCUAGAGCAUGACUGGCUAACUGGAGAGGGAAGGAAAAGUUUAGAUCUGGUUACUGGAGCAAGUCUCAAAGAGAAACUCUGAAAGCUUCCAGAAUCACAGGUAUAAGAUAAGGAUAGCAUUGACAUUUGCUGGGAGUUACAGUGAUAGUUUCAUCUCAGCAGUUCAUUUUUUUCUUCAGUCACUGCUGGUUUUCUUUGACUAUUAUAGUUGCCAGGAAGAUCCUUGCUCUUCUUACUUUAAAACCAGCAUUUAAGUGGCAAUUUGGAUGUAAUAGGAUGAGACCAAAUUUAUCUAAUUAUUACAGUAGUAAUACAUUUAAGAGUUAAAAAUGUGUUUUUAUAUAUCCACAUAUGAUAACAAAAGAUUCAAUUCCCAAGCCUAAAUUUUGAAGCAUGUGGUAUUGUCAAAUCUAGCUUACCAUCUUUUUUGGGGGUACUUGCAACCAUAGUAAAGGAAGAUGGAAUAGACUUUAGUUAACUUUAAUUAUAAUUAUAUGUUAAAUAAGGCACAUAACCAGUUUCCAAGGUCAUCAUGGUUGCUUAAAGUCUUUCCCCUUCUGUACUCCAUGGAAAUAUUCUCAGUAAACCAAAAACAAAAAUGGAAAAAUAAUCACCAACCCCCAUCCCGACACACACACAGAGUCCAAAGCAAAAGUCAGUGUGUAUUGAAUUUAACAAGUAAUGCAGUUUGGGAUGCUUUUGCUACAUUUUGGUGGCAUUUUAACUAGUUAUCUGAAUAUUUAUUAAUCGUACUUCCUCUUGUAAAGUUAACUACUUACUUUUUUGUUGUUGUUUUUUUAACAUCAGGUUCUGUAUCUAAUAGGAGAUGUAACACUUUAUUUCAUGGCAGGUUUUUAUUGCAGAGACUUGAAGUCUUAGUUUUUUAAACUGGCACAUAAAACACUUUUUGCUGUUAUUUUUAUUUAUGUCAAUACUGCAGAGUAUCUUUAUGCCUUAUUCAAGUGGAUUCUGAGCCUGUAUGUCACAAUGUAAACACUGGAGGUUCACUCACCUACGCACUCACCCACCACCUCUGAAAGAAACAGAAACUGCAGAGAAAGACAGCAUCUUAGCUCAUUUUGUUUUUAAAUGAGGUUUUAGACGCUUGCCACUUCCUAAGGGAAAUCCUAAAACAGAGCAAGUGAUGCUCCCAGGUAUCACUGUGAACUUUUUUCUUUCAAAGUGUGAAUUUUUACACUGGCUUUUUCAUUUUUUUAAAGUAAUUGAAGCUUGUGGCUUUACAACUUAGUGUUUUUUGCUAUCCAGAUAACAAGUUUCAUUGUUUAGAACCCAGUGACACUUAAUAGGUAGAUAAAUUGUCCUUUAAAAUAUCCCAGAUGAUAUACACAAUAUGGUACAUUUGUGCUCUCUCUCUCUGUUUUUCUCUCUUUCUCUUUCUAGUUAGAUCAAGAUAACGAUGACUUGUACCCUCCCUGAUUCUGUUACAGUAGGGCCCGGGCAGAUCUGUGUUUGUUAAACAGGCCUUGUUUGUGCAUGCUUUGCUAUGAAUGAAGUUCCUUUAAGGACAAAGAAAAGCACACUUUUCUUCUUUUGAGCAUAUCUGCUUUUACUUUAAAUCUGCUAAUUUCUAAAAUGUAGAGUCCUUCACCAAUCCCAGAGACUCAAUUUGGAAAUGAACUGAUUUCAAGCCGUUACUGUGAAUAAAGCACCCCAGCAUUUUGUAUAAGCUCUUAAUUAAACCUGUACAGCUUCUUUACCUGAUUUAAGAAAGGGAGACAAGCAAUAGGGGGGAAUAAGCUUCUUCAAAAUUCAUUCCAAGCACAAAAGAAAUUUUUUCCCUUUGCAUAUAAACUUGACAUCAGUUGAUUCUGUUGGGGUCGGGGUGGGUAUGCAGGGAUUGCCUUUUAUUAUCAAGUGAUUUAUUUCAAGAGCCUUUGAGGGGAUUCAGGUGAAGGAACCCCCAUCUGUGCUGGAGAGUUGGAUACUCCUUUAAAUAGCCCCCACCACAGUCAUAACAAUAAUGAUAAUGCUGGAUUAUUUGUUAAGCCAAGGUUGUCUGCCUCAUAUCCAUCAUGCUGUUUGCAAUAUUCUUGCUUUCAAUCAAUUUAUACUGAGUGUAACUUUAGGAUUUCUGCUAUUAAAUGCAUGCUCUCUAUCCUGCUUCAGUUUCUGGCUUUGCUUUGUCUGUUUCAAAAUAUGUAGCUUCCUCUUUUGUACAACAAAAAACUCAUUCUCACUUUUACUAAAUAUACUGUAGGAGUCAUCAUUGAUGUUAUUUUUCUCUUAUGUAUCUGUAAAGAUUUUUGGCAUAUGAAUGUAAUAUUAAAGUCAAUGAUGCUAUAACUUGCGAUGUUUGCAUCAUGUCAACCUUUUUGAAGGAGUGAAAAAGCCCUACUAUGUUUUUAAAUAGCAAGUGUAAGCUCAGUGCUAGAGUGGAUAUACACACCGCAUGUUUUCAUAUGUGGCACUUUUAUGUAUCAUGUUGGGUUAUUGUUCUAGACUGGACUGUUAAAUACUAUGUUUGAGGCUGGGUUGUCAUUUUUAUAACUGUCUUGGUGUUUUAUGGCCAUUAUUUAUUACUUUUGAUACACAGAAUGAGCUGCAUGCAUUUAUAGAGCAAUAAGAGGAUGUAUUUAAUGUGCCUUGUUUUUAACUGAAUAAGAACUGGAAGCAUGAAUCAAUAAAACUGAUUAAAAUGGUCUAUUUGCUAGCAUUUUGAUGUUACUUGCAGUCAGAUAACUUUGAUUACUGUUGAAGUUUAAAAAAAGUUUGAAAAUAUUUUUACAAACUGUGUUUUUGAUGACACAAAAGUGAAAUAUCUACAGAGAUAGAUGUAAUUUUAUAAGACUGCCAGAAUUAUUUGUAUUAAUUUGUUGCUGUAGCCUUUAGGGCAUGACUUCUGUAUUUGUGCAAUCCUAUUCUACAAUUACAUUCAUCCUAUUACAACUCA